UGUUGGGGUCCUAUUCAUCCUUCAAAGCUCAGCUCAGAGGUCUCUUCUUUGACAGUCUUGAGUCCCAGCCAGAGGGGGAACGAUAAUCCUGGAUGGGAGGUAGGGAGCCAGACCUCCAGAGGGCAAGUGAGAAGGCCAUGGGAGGCGGAACCCAGCGAAGGCGAGAGAAUGAAGACACGCAUCGGGCUGUGGCCAGACGGUUGGCAGCCAGGGACCUAGCCAAGCCUCCCUGCCCCCGACGCCCGCGUCCAGGGAUCGUCGAUGACAGUUCGCCUGUCGGGACAUCGGAUCAGGCGGCCGCCCCUGGGGAGAUGAGCAAGUCAAGCCACAGCUGACCUGUGAAAGGCCGUGUAACAGUGACUGGAAGAACCAGGAAGCCUAAACAAAUCAGGAGUAUGAAAGGGAGAGAACACAGUGCUGCGGGAGUUUAUGCCAAAGGCACGGACCCAGGCAUCAGCGUUUAAGUUUAAACUGUCUAGAGGAAAGAUGGAUACUAUGAUGCUGAAUGUGCGGAAUCUGUUUGAGCAGCUUGUGCGCCGGGUGGAGAUUCUCAGUGAAGGAAAUGAAGUCCAAUUUAUCCAGUUGGCGAAGGACUUUGAGGAUUUCCGUAAAAAGUGGCAGAGGACUGACCAUGAGCUGGGGAAAUACAAGGAUCUUUUGAUGAAAGCAGAGACUGAGCGAAGUGCUCUGGAUGUUAAGCUGAAGCAUGCACGUAAUCAGGUGGAUGUAGAGAUCAAACGGAGACAGAGAGCUGAGGCUGACUGCGAAAAGCUGGAACGACAGAUUCAGCUGAUUCGAGAGAUGCUCAUGUGUGACACAUCUGGCAGCAUUCAACUAAGCGAGGAGCAAAAAUCAGCUCUGGCUUUUCUCAACAGAGGCCAACCAUCCAGCAGCAAUGCUGGGAACAAAAGACUAUCAACCAUUGAUGAAUCUGGUUCCAUUUUAUCAGAUAUCAGCUUUGACAAGACUGAUGAAUCACUGGAUUGGGACUCUUCUUUGGUGAAGACUUUCAAACUGAAGAAGAGAGAAAAGAGGCGCUCUACUAGCCGACAGUUUGUUGAUGGUCCCCCUGGACCUGUAAAGAAAACUCGUUCCAUUGGCUCUGCAGUAGACCAGGGGAAUGAAUCCAUAGUUGCAAAAACUACAGUGACUGUUCCCAAUGAUGGCGGGCCCAUCGAAGCUGUGUCCACUAUUGAGACUGUGCCAUAUUGGACCAGGAGCCGAAGGAAAACAGGUACUUUACAACCUUGGAACAGUGACUCCACCCUGAACAGCAGGCAGCUGGAGCCAAGAACUGAGACAGACAGUGUGGGCACGCCACAGAGUAAUGGAGGGAUGCGCCUGCAUGACUUUGUUUCUAAGACGGUUAUUAAACCUGAAUCCUGUGUUCCAUGUGGAAAGCGGAUAAAAUUUGGCAAAUUAUCUCUGAAGUGUCGAGACUGUCGUGUGGUCUCUCAUCCAGAAUGUCGGGACCGCUGUCCCCUUCCCUGCAUUCCUACCCUGAUAGGAACACCUGUCAAGAUUGGAGAGGGAAUGCUGGCAGACUUUGUGUCCCAGACUUCUCCAAUGAUCCCCUCCAUUGUUGUGCAUUGUGUAAAUGAGAUUGAGCAAAGAGGUCUGACUGAGACAGGCCUGUAUAGGAUCUCUGGCUGUGACCGCACAGUAAAAGAGCUGAAAGAGAAAUUCCUCAGAGUGAAAACUGUACCCCUCCUCAGCAAAGUGGAUGAUAUCCAUGCUAUCUGUAGCCUUCUAAAAGACUUUCUUCGAAACCUCAAAGAACCUCUUCUGACCUUUCGCCUUAACAGAGCCUUUAUGGAAGCAGCAGAAAUCACAGAUGAAGACAACAGCAUAGCUGCCAUGUACCAAGCUGUUGGUGAACUGCCCCAGGCCAACAGGGACACAUUAGCUUUCCUCAUGAUUCACUUGCAGAGAGUGGCUCAGAGUCCACAUACUAAAAUGGAUGUUGCCAAUCUGGCUAAAGUCUUUGGCCCUACAAUAGUGGCCCAUGCUGUGCCCAAUCCAGACCCAGUGACAAUGUUACAGGACAUCAAGCGUCAACCCAAGGUGGUUGAGCGCCUGCUUUCCUUGCCUCUGGAGUAUUGGAGUCAGUUCAUGAUGGUGGAGCAAGAGAACAUUGACCCCCUACAUGUCAUUGAAAACUCAAAUGCCUUUUCAACACCACAGACACCAGAUAUUAAAGUGAGUUUACUGGGACCUGUGACCACUCCUGAACAUCAGCUUCUCAAGACUCCUUCAUCUAGUUCCCUGUCACAGAGAGUCCGUUCCACCCUCACCAAGAACACUCCUAGAUUUGGGAGCAAAAGCAAGUCUGCCACUAACCUAGGACGACAAGGCAACUUUUUUGCUUCUCCAAUGCUCAAGUGAAGUCACAUCUGCCUGUUACUUCCCAGCAUUGACUGACUAUAAGAAAGGACACAUCUGUACUCUGCUCUGCAGCCUCCUGUACUCAUUACUACUUUUAGCAUUCUCCAGGCUUUUACUCAAGUUUAAUUGUGCAUGAGGGUUUUAUUAAAACUAUAUAUAUCUCCCCUUCCUUCUCCUCAAGUCACAUAAUAUCAGCACUUUGUGCUGGUCAUUGUUGGGAGCUUUUAGAUGAGACAUCUUUCCAGGGGUAGAAGGGUUAGUAUGGAAUUGGUUGUGAUUCUUUUUGGGGAAGGGGGUUAUUGUUCCUUUGGCUUAAAGCCAAAUGCUGCUCAUAGAAUGAUCUUUCUCUAGUUUCAUUUAGAACUGAUUUCCGUGAGACAAUGACAGAAACCCUACCUAUCUGAUAAGAUUAGCUUGUCUCAGGGUGGGAAGUGGGAGGGCAGGGCAAAGAAAGGAUUAGACCAGAGGAUUUAGGAUGCCUCCUUCUAAGAACCAGAAGUUCUCAUUCCCCAUUAUGAACUGAGCUAUAAUAUGGAGCUUUCAUAAAAAUGGGAUGCAUUGAGGACAGAACUAGUGAUGGGAGUAUGCGUAGCUUUGAUUUGGAUGAUUAGGUCUUUAAUAGUGUUGAGUGGCACAACCUUGUAAAUGUGAAAGUACAACUCGUAUUUAUCUCUGAUGUGCUGCUGGCUGAACUUUGGGUUCAUUUGGGGUCAAAGCCAGUUUUUCUUUUAAAAUUGAAUUCAUUCUGAUGCUUGGCCCCCAUACCCCCAACCUUGUCCAGUGGAGCCCAACUUCUAAAGGUCAAUAUAUCAUCCUUUGGCAUCCCAACUAACAAUAAAGAGUAGGCUAUAAGGGAAGAUUGUCAAUAUUUUGUGGUAAGAAAAGCUACAGUCAUUUUUUCUUUGCACUUUGGAUGCUGAAAUUUUUCCCAUGGAACAUAGCCACAUCUAGAUAGAUGUGAGCUUUUUCUUCUGUUAAAAUUAUUCUUAAUGUCUGUAAAAACGAUUUUCUUCUGUAGAAUGUUUGACUUCGUAUUGACCCUUAUCUGUAAAACACCUAUUUGGGAUAAUAUUUGGAAAAAAAGUAAAUAGCUUUUUCAAAAUGAA